GGUGAGUGAGUGCAGACAGAUGGGGCCUGGUGCCCUUGAGCAGUUCCCGGGUCUCAGCUGCCACACAUCUCAUAGCCGGUGAUGCUGGGGGAAGCUUACGCAGUCACAGUACUGGCUUCUUCCUCUUUUUCUUUCCAUACAAGUGGCUUAGGGAUGGGGUAGAGUAGUUGACUUAUUUGGAUGAAAACCACUAUCUUCUGUCAGAAACUCAAAAGGAAUCAUUGCUGGCAUGGUAACCUAAAGAAAAACAACCAGACAAGUGCCCAACGACACUUAAAAAGGUGAUUUAUUAUCUUGCCAAGUUUAGGCUGGGCAUGGUGACUCAUGCCUCUAAUCCCAGCAUUUUGGGAGGCUGAGGCUGGUGGAUCACCGGAGGCCAGGACUUUGAGACCAGCCUGACCAAUAUGGCAAAACCUCGUCCCUACUAAAAAUACAAAAAUUAGCCGGGCAUGGUGGUGUGAGCCUGUAGUCCCAGCUACUCAGGAGGCUGAGACAGGAGAAUUGCUUAGAUUCAGGAGGUGGGGGUUUUAGUGGGCCGAGAUCACGCCAUUGCACUCCAGACUGUGCGACAGAGCGAGACUCUGUCAAAAAAAAAAAAAAAAAAUUAUCCUGCAAAAUUUGAAAAGGAAAUUCAAAUCAACAGCUUCUAAACUACUUUUUAACAUGACUCAUAAUAAUACAUUCUAUAGUACAUAUGUAUGUUCUAUAACUUUGAAUAAAAGAGUUAACCACAUCACAUUUAUUUUAUAACAUGUAAUACAUAUUUUUUAUUCUCCUUCAUUUGUUUUGAAUGCUCUGUGCAGUCUACAAAAAGUCCAAUAGUAAUAAUUAAAUUAGUCAUUAAGUUGAACAUUAUCUUGUCUUUUAAAAUGAUAAUCUCAAAAAUGAUCUUUUAUUUUUGAGAUUUAUAUAGAUACACACACACACACACACACACACACACACACACACACACACAUAUUUUUUGAGACAGAGUUUCACUCUGUCCCCCAGGCUGGAGUGCAAUGGCACAAUCUUGGCUCACUGCAACCUCUGUCUCCCGGGUUCAAGCAAUUCCUCUGCCUCAGCCUCUGAGUAGCUGGGACUACAGGUGUGUGCCACCAUGCCCAGCUAAUUUUUGUAUUCUUAGUAGAGAUGGGGUUUCACCAUAUUGGCCAGGCUCGUGUCAACUCCUGACCUCGUGAUCUGCCCACCGCGGCCUCCCAAAGUGCUGGGACUAUAGGUGUGAGCCGCUGCACCCGGUCCAAGUAAAAUUAUUUUAACAAUAUACUAUGAAGAGAAAAACACUGGCUAUGAAAGAAUAUGCAUAGUUUUACCCUGUUUAAAAAUAAAGAUUGAAAGAAUACAUAUGCAAAUAAGUUUACUUUUAUUUUUGGUAACACUUUACUGCAUUGUCUGAAUAUUGACAAUCAGUAUGCAUUAUGAAGCUACCUGGCUAACAUUGUGUACUCACUGUGUGUGCCAGGCCCUGGGUUCAAUGCUCUACAUGCACUUAUAUUUCAUUUAAUUCUCUCUGCAACCUGAGAUGGUAUAGCCACCUCAUUUUACAGAGUUGAAACUGAGGCUCAGAGACUGAAAGUUAAGCCUGAGGUUGCAGUCAAUAAGAGGCAGAGCUGGAACUGAAACCUACCUGUGUCUGACCACCAGUUCGUGUUCUGACGGCAGGCUAGUCUGCAUCACAGAGUGUGGAGUAGAUGGUGCAUGCCUGCUAGGAUGGGCUAGGUAUCACUGUAGGUAAGAAACAGCCCCAAACUAUGGAAAUGUACACCACUGAAGGCUCUUUUCCUGCCCAUGCUGCACAUCCUCCAUGGCUCUCCUGUGCCCUGUGCCCCACAUGCCCUCAUCCUGCCACGAGAAUAAAGGAGCAGCCUCCAUAUGGGAGCUGUCAGCUGCUCUAAGAGAUGAAGGAGAGAGUGGCCCGUCUCAAUGGCUCCCAACUCUUUUGCCUCGAGGUGACACGCUUCACUUCCACGCACAUCUCCUGGGUCAAAGCAAAUCCCAUGGGUACAUCCACUUUCAAGUGGCCCAGGAGAGAACCUGAAAUACUCGGUGGACUCCAUUAAGGCCGUCAUAUGGUGUCAGCCUGCAUGGGAGACUGUGGAGGGGCAGAGGAGGAGAGUGGGGAACUGAUGGGAAAUGACAGGAGGACUAAGUCACCGCAGAUUUGCUUUAUCUUCAGCCAGGUGGAGUUUGUCCCAGAGCCGCACAAAAUCAUCACCAGCAUGAUUAAACGGAGUAGACUUCAGAAAAAGCAGUUUGGUCGGAUGUAAUCAGCAGUGAACUCAGAAUCAAUUGAGUGACAUUGAGUCAGUAAAUCUCUGACUGCCUCAGUUACCCCAUAUGAUAGUUUUGAGGAUGGGAACAUUGAGAGAGUUGAUUUGGAAGGAUAUCAAGAGUAAAAAUUCCAACAUUUUUAGUUCCUUUAAGUUAAAUCCAGGCACUGUCUUUCCUGCAAGUCUCCUGUUCCUUUCAGAUUGCACAGGUGAGAGUGCUCAGAUUAGGGCUGGAGGUUGUAAACCAUUGCUCCCACACUGACAGUGCCCCCGUGUCGUGCGUGUAUUCUGCGCAUUUUCCUGUGCUAAACACUCUCCCAAAACAUCGUGGGGCCUGAUUCUUCCUCUUUGUUCCAAUGGCCCUGGGUGACUCAAGUGCCCAUUCAAUGACCAGGACACAGAGGUCUUAGAGAGAUGCUCCUUGAGGCCCCAGGUGCGAGCCUGUACCCUGCCGGAGCAUGAGGCAAGGGACAGGGCAUCGUCUGUGGGGAUAGUGGGGGUAGUGGGGGUAGUGGUCAGCCAGAUUUGGUGACUCUACUUGCUCACCAGACGAUCCUACACCUGCCACCUCCGAUGGAUCCACUGCCUCUGUGCCUGCCUGUACUGCUGAUGCUCCAGUGGAUAACUCAGCAUCCCAGCCUAGGCCCAAUGCCACUGAAGAUGGACCUGCCCCCUGGGGACCCAGGAGUCCUACCACUCAGCUGUCCCCAGGAGUGCCCAGACCCUCAUUCUUAUCCAGGACCUAGGAGCCCUACCCCUGGCCUUCCCUCAUCAGCCGUAAAUGAUGAUUUACUGCUGUUACCAUCAUCACUGCCUUCAGUGACCAAGGGCCUUCCAAGGUGCCAGCUCUGGAACGAAGGAUGCCCUUGGGAGGUGAUGACACUCAGGUUGAUGGACGGAUGGCUACAUGGAUGUGAUGGAGAUGGUUUACUAUCGGGACCUUCCGCACCCUGCUGAUGUUUUGUUGCUUAGGAUAUGAAUGGCUGAGCGGAGGCUGUAAAACCUGGCACUCUGCUUGGGUAUGAGGUUCUUCCUGCCAUCCUGCCAUCAUUUGUUUUUUAUGUUUUGUCGCCAUAAGUGACCUUGAGGAACCCUGGGAGCUCAGGAAGGAAGGAGCGCCCAGAAGCAGGGACAGGGAGCUGGUUGGGGAGGACCAGAAAUCAGGUUAUCAAUACUCUGGCUGACCAUCAUCAUCGUGGGACUGACUUUGGUGGAAGUCCUUGGUUACAUGUCAUUAUUGCAUUUCCGACAAGUUAUAAAGUUGUCAUUACCCUCUGGAUAGUUUACCUUUGGGUGUCUCUCCUGAAGACUAUCUUCUGGUCUCGAAAUGGACAUGAUGGAUCCACGGAUGUACAGCAGAGAGCCUGGAGGUCCAACCGCCGUAGACAGGAAGGGCUGAGGUCCAUUUGUAUGCACACAAAGAAAAGAGUUUCUUCCUUUCGAGGAAAUAAAAUUGUCCUGAAAGACGUCAUUACUCUACGGAGACAUGUGGAAACAAAAGUUAGAGCUAAAAUCCGUAAGAGGAAGGUGACAACGAAAAUCAACCAUCAUGACAAAAUCAAUGGAAAGAGGAAGACCGCCAGAAAACAGAAAAUGUUUCAACGUGCGCAAGAGUUGCGGCGGCGAGCAGAGGACUACCACAAAUGCAAAAUCCCCCCUUCUGCAAGAAAGGCUCUUUGCAACUGGGUCAGAAUGGCGGCAGCGGAGCAUCGUCAUUCUUCAGGAUUGCCCUACUGGCCCUACCUCACAGCUGAAACUUUAAAAAACAGGAUGGGCCACCAGCCACCUCCUCCAACUCAACAACAUUCUAUAACUGAUAACUCCCUGAGCCUCAAGACACCUCCCGAGUGUCUGCUCACUCCCCUUCCACCCUCAGCGGAUGAUAAUCUCAAGACACCUCCCGAGUGUGUGCUCACUCCCCUUCCACCCUCAGCGGAUGAUAAUCUCA